AGAUGCGGCCGCGGCGGCGCGGAGCUCGGGCGGCCGUGGAGGAACUCAGCCUCGGCCGCAGGAGGCGCCGGGAGCGGAGCCGCCGGGAGUCGCGCAACAGGUUUCCUUCUCCAUCGCUGCGCCCACAGGGGACGCGCGCCCUGCCGGGAGAGGGGCUUCUCGGUUCGCACUCUCGCUCCCAGUCCAGUAGGGUGACUGUGUCAAAAACACCAGAAUGGGUACUUCUUGACUUGAACUUGGCGGUGUCACUCAGUAGCCAGGAAAGACGGAGAAAUUGAUAGAGCCUUCGAGGAGUCCCUUCGAAGCCCACACUCCGCUGACACCAGCUGAGAUCUGUAUUACUUCCUGUGGUUCUCACGCACUUGUUUCAGCCGUUUCUCAGCAGAGGGAGGAGCUGUUAUUUACAGCUUACUGACUCUGAAGGUAUAUUUUUUGCAUAUGUAAGGAGGUCAUACAUCAUUUUUUCUCUCAUCUGAUAUACGGAAUCCUUCAAAGUCACCACGUUGUUCAUCAUCAUCACUGAACCCACCAGAGCUUGUGCCAGGCAAAAUGAAAGACCGGCUAGCAGAACUUCUGGACUUGUCCAAGCAAUAUGACCAGCAGUUCCCAGACGGGGACGAUGAGUUUGACUCGCCCCACGAGGACAUCGUGUUCGAGACGGACCACAUCCUGGAGUCCCUGUACCGAGACAUCCGGGACAUUCAGGAUGAAAACCAGCUGCUGGUGGCCGACGUGAAGCGGCUGGGAAAGCAGAACGCCCGCUUCCUCACGUCCAUGCGGCGCCUCAGCAGCAUCAAGCGCGACACCAACUCCAUCGCCAAGGCCAUCAAGGCCCGGGGCGAGGUCAUCCACUGCAAGCUGCGCGCCAUGAAGGAGCUGAGCGAGGCGGCUGAGGCCCAGCACGGCCCGCACUCGGCAGUGGCGCGCAUUUCGCGGGCGCAGUACAACGCGCUCACCCUCACCUUCCAGCGCGCCAUGCACGACUACAACCAGGCCGAGAUGAAGCAGCGCGACAACUGCAAGAUCCGCAUCCAGCGCCAGCUGGAGAUCAUGGGCAAGGAAGUCUCGGGCGACCAGAUCGAGGACAUGUUCGAGCAGGGUAAGUGGGACGUGUUUUCCGAGAACUUGCUGGCCGACGUGAAGGGCGCGCGGGCCGCCCUCAACGAGAUCGAGAGCCGCCACCGCGAACUGCUGCGCCUGGAGAGCCGCAUCCGCGACGUACACGAGCUCUUCUUGCAGAUGGCGGUGCUGGUGGAGAAGCAGGCCGACACCCUGAACGUCAUCGAGCUCAACGUACAAAAGACGGUCGACUACACCGGCCAGGCCAAGGCGCAGGUGCGGAAGGCCGUGCAGUACGAGGAGAAGAACCCCUGCCGGACCCUCUGCUGCUUCUGCUGUCCCUGCCUCAAGUAGCAGGCCGGCCCGGGCCGCCACCGCCCAUCCCAGACCAUGGAGCGCGCUGGGAAGGACGCACCAAAGCCGGGAGCUCUGCCCUGCAGGGAGUUGCCCCAACCCUUUCCGGAACUCAGUCUUUAGAAAAGAAACGCCAGGUUCAAGAAUUGCAAACCAGCCUGUGCUUGGAAAGAUGGUUAGUUGAUACCGUCCGAUGAUUCUUCAGUAAAGAUAGAUUCCCACAAAGUUGUGCAAUGUCAUUAUAUGACACCUUGCACUCUUACCGUCUUGACAGAAGCCAAGUAAGGAACUGAAGUUGUAUCUGACUGUAGGGUGAAUGUCUGAGGCCUGCCUCCUAAUAAAGACUCAAGGAGGAAGUCAAUUGGGCAUCUGCUAAUAGAAUGAACUCAUGAUGGAAACUUCAGUUCAUUUACUUUGUCCUGAAAAUUCCCUGGUUCUGUUCCAUUUUGAGCGAAAUUGGCCUUGGGAAAAACCACGUUCUUCCUUUCCGAUUCUUCAUCCGGUCUACGCUAUGCAAUUCCUCCCCAAAUAUAGAUCUUAUUUCUGCUCAUUUCCCCUACUUAUUAAAAUCACACCAAACACUUACUAUUUUCUUAUCUCUUUCACUUUUUAAAUAUCUUUCACCAGGUUAUAUUUUGGUAUUAUUUUUCCAAACAUUUUUAAGCACUGAAUAUCGAACAAGCACUCAAAUUGAAGUAUCAGUCAUGUUUUGUGUAUUUUUCGCUGAUAAAAAUUAUUUAACAUUUAUAUUUUUACUUGAUUACAUAUGCACAUGUAUGUAAAUGUAAAAUACUAAUAUUCACUAAUAUAUGUACAUAAUGAUCAAUUGGUUUAACUUCUUUUAUGUAAGUAUGGUAUAUAAAUUUCAAGACGAACACUUUUCUGGCUCUUGGUAUUGGUUUGCUUGUUUUGAGUUUGUUUCACUCCAGUUUGCCCCUUCCUAGUCCAGUUUGGGUCAAACUUCAUGUUAAACAACUCUGCAUUGGUUAUGGCGGUAGACAUAUGGCGGUAGAAAAUGUAUACGGAGCUAGAGACAACUAACAUUCUUGGAAAUACUGCUUUUGUUUUACUGUGGACCAUUCCUUCCAUGCAUUGAAAUGGAGAAAUUCAAAGUAAAAGAAUUCUGUUUUUCAAGCAAGCUUAAUAAACAUUACAUUAUACACAUAUUUUUAUACAUUUCUGGCUUGACCAUUUAGUUUACUUUCUCAAUUAUUGUUAAAAUUUUUCUUUUUCCUUUUUUUUUUUUUUUUUUUGAGAUGGAGUCUCACUGUGUUGCCCAGGCUGGAGUGCAGUGGCAGGAUCUUGGCUCAUUGCAACCUCUGUCUCCCAGGUUCGAGCGAUUCUCCUGACUCAGCCUCCUGAGAAGUUGGGACUCUGGGCGCGUGCCACAAUGUCUGGCUAAUUUUUUAUGUUUUUAGUAAAGACGGUGUUUCACCGUGUUAGCCAGGAUGGUCUUGAUCUCCUGACCUCGUGAUCCGCCCGCCUCAGCCUCCCAUAGUGCUGGGAUUACAGGUGUGAGCCACCAUGCCUGGCCUUUUUUCCCCCCUUUUGAGACAGGGUCUCCCUUUGUCACCCAGGCUGAAGUGCAGUGGCAUAAUCAUGGCUUACUGCAGCCUUAAACUCCCAGGCUCAAGUGAUCCUCCCACCUCAGCCUACAAAUAGCUGAGACUACAGAUAUGUGCCACCAUGCCCGGCUAAUUUUUGUAUUUUCUGUAGAGACAGGGUUUGCCAUGUGGCCCAGGCUGGUCUCAAACUUGUGAGCUUGAGCAAUCCGCCCACCUUGGCCUCCCAAAGUGCUGAGAUUACAGGCCUGAGCCACUGACCCUGGCCAAAUUUUUUUUCUACUAGCUACUGAGGCUGCCACAUCUGGAUGGAACUGAGUGGAGGGGGAAAAGAAUGAAAAACUCAAAAGAAUUCCCAUGAGGGUGUCUUGCUUUCUCUCCUGAGUUACAAUACUUUAGCAAAAUCAUGAGGCUUUAGAGAUAUGGUGUAGUCUGCAAACUUCUUAAUGCCCUUACCCACAUUUACCAUGUUUCCUGGCCUUCCUCUGUGUCAACUCUUAGCUCUUCCUAAUCAUUAUUUAAUACAUGAGUGAGUUUAGUAGUGAUCAUAUUUCUCAGGUCCUUUAGAAGCUGGAAUUUUAAAAGAAUUAGAAGGAGGAGUAUGUGAAUUCUUUGGAGCUCACUGCCUGACUUGCUUAUGACCAGGAAAAUCUAUCCCCUGUAUCUAAUUUUAAUUUCAUGGUUAAAUUUGAGAAUUGUGGAAACCAAGUUCCACAAGGCUAUUCUCAUAUUUCUCCCAAUUUCUUUUUCAGCCAACUCCAAGGAUAUGUAUCACCUUUGACUUAAUUUGCUUUCUCUAAGGGAAAGGGGAAAAAAUGUUCACAUAGCUCCACUGCAAUGUUUUUUAUAAUAGAGGAGAGAUAUUGUAAAUAGAGACUGCCAGCCAGUUUCCACAAAAAAACGAAGAGUUCAUAAAUUUGACAUGUUUGAACCCAUAAAGCAUUUUCUUUGCUUGGAACCAUUAUAAAAGUAAGUGAGUUUUCAGGCUCUAUAUACAUUUUAAUUCCUCACGUUUUAUAUUGGAGAGUUCGGUACAGACUGUCCAUUACUGCACCAAAAGAAUGAGUGAACUGUUACCUAUAGGGAAAGAACACUUCUUCUUCCUGCUGUUUGGGAACCAUCUCAGUGUGGCGUAAUGGUUAGGAGUACAGAUUCCAGAUCCUGUUUCUUAGAUUUAAAUCUUGACUCUGCCACAUACUAGCUGUCUGACUGAACCUUGGUUUUUCUGUGCUUCAGUUUCCUCAUCUGUAAAACGGAGAUAACAGUACUUACCUCAUAGAGCUGUUGUGAAAAGUGAUGACUGAAUAUGUAAAAGCACCUAGAACAGUGCCUGGCACAUGCUAAGUGCUUUGUUCAUUAUUGUUGUUAUUAUGUAAUUUUCUCUCAGACUGAGAGCACUGUUAGUGACCCAAGUAAAUUUAUAGUUUUUAAGUACAGAGGAAAAAUAAAGCCUAUUUUUUGUUAACAGUCUUAAUAAAUAAUAAAAUGGAAUAAAGAAACCAAGACCCCAUCUUCUGUGAAUAUUAGGGCUUUUUUUUUUUUGACAGUCAUAAAGAUGUUUUCACUAUGGCAUUUCUAUCCCUGUGUAUAUCCAAACAUGUCCUGAAGAAGAAAUGAGAUGUUCCACCAAAAACACGUAAGCAGGAAGCAGCUGUUCUGCUCAGCUUGGCAGGUGUUCUUUCCUAAUUCUUCCCAAGCUGUGAGUCAGAAAGUCCUGGAAGGAGUUGUAGGAAGUUGUAGAGGCUGGGUCACUGACCUAAGAGAAGGCAUCAUUUGGCCCACUGCACGUCCUGGCCUAUUCACCAAAGCCCUUCCUGGCUCUGACUGCCACACCAGGCAGUGGGUGAAAUGCUGGCUUUUUCCUUAAGAAAUUGUGUUCUAGUGCCACCAAGAGAUGCUGUAGAGCUGGCUUUACCAAUCUCAUGAUGCUUGCUUGGCAACUCUGAAAGGUGACUUUGGCCAAGAAGACCUUGUGGCAAUUCUGCAAAUUUUAUACACUCAUAUCUUUUAGGGUACAAAAUGAAAGAACAAAUCACAAAGAACAAUAGAUCCUUCAGGAGCUGAAGGUAAGAAUCUUUUAUAGCUAUUUUAACAUAUACAGUGACUACUUUCUACUAGCCAAAUAUCAAAUUUUACAACUACCACCAAGCCACAGAUUAUAGGUGGUAACAACUCCAGAAAUGUCCUAACUAGGAAAGGUGCUCAUCUAGUAUGCAUCGGUAUCCAGGAUAAUAUGAGUUAGAAUUUUAAAAAUGUCAGUCAUUCAAAAAUAUUUGAACUGUGACAUCACAGAAGUAAUUUUAUGGCCUUUUAAGGUAACAACUUAAAAAGAGAACAGUACUCUUUUUAUAUCAAUGCCUUUACAUUUAUUUAAAAACAGUCCUAAUGCUUUAUAGUUAAAUGUCAUAUGCAGAUAUGUUCAGGCUCUAACAUAUAAAGUUCCUAACUUGACAGGAAACUACUGAAGAUUGUGUACAGCUUAAAAAAAAAAAUAGGGUAACUAUAGUCUUGAUUUUUAUGUAUAAAUUCUAUCAUUCUAUAUUUUACCAUCAGACAUAUUUCUACUCCUUUCUUUGAAGUAUGCGAAGUAUCUCCAACUGCAGCAUGCAACUCAUUCAUUUGUAAUCAAGACGAUAGUUUGAAACACCCAAUUGUAAUCAGAGCAACAGUUGACUUCCUUUUGAUAGCGGAGUUGAAAAUCAUUGCAAUUAAUAAAAUGGGGCUAUUAGAAAUGGAAAACGAAUAGGAUCUAGAAUGUAACUUCAUCAUAUAAAUGAUGAGUGUCUUUGUUAUCAACACGUUAUUAAGAAUGGGCAAGAUGUCCUUAUAUACUAGAAGCUUUUGUAAAGUCAUGUGUCUAUUGAUAAUAAAGAUUUUCGGAACUGA